GUUUCCGCUGGCGGCGGCGGCGGCGGCGGUGCCGGAGCGCGAGCAGAGCGGAGACCCCCAGGUCCUGCGGGCGCGGAAUAUCCUGGAACCUUCUUUUGUUUGUCAGCAGCCAAGGUGUUUCCAGGAAGUUCAGAGAGAACAGAAUUUAAGAAGUGCAACAUGGCCAGGGGCUGCCUCUGCUGCUUGAAGUACAUGAUGUUCCUCUUCAAUUUGAUAUUCUGGGAUCCUCCAGUUGGUGAGAAUGGGCUGACUGGGCUCGCAGAGGGCGGAUCAGUUUUCUCGUGCCAGGAAGUCGUGGAAUCGGGAGGUCAUCUGGCUCGUCCUGCGCUGAGCAUUUGAACACAGGGCUGUCAAGGGAGAGGUGGUGACACUGAAAGGGGACUGCCUCACCUGGACUACGUGUGUGCUCAGUGUGCUGGAACUCACUGCCUGGACAAAGCUGCCCUAGAUUUUGCCAUUCCUGGAGCUCACAGGCCUGGAGUGAGCGGCUGCCUGCCGCGGGGCUGGGUCGGGACAGGAGCGCUGGGUUCCAGGGUGGACGAACUCCUGUUGGAUUUGCCUCUUCGGACCUCCAGUUCCUUGCUUAGUGGUGGGGGGAGAAUCUUCCCUGUUAGCCCAUUUCCCACUUCAGGGUAGCAAGAAAUGGAAGUCGUUUCUGGGCCUGGGCAGGAGAUGGGGCCACAGCCACAGCAGUCAGUUGAUUUGAACACGCCCUCCCCCCUGCAGGGGAGGGCCUUCACGCCCUCUAAGCAGGUAAUGAGGGGGCGGGCUGCCGUAUUAAGCACCCUGGCUACGCUGGGGAGAAGCUCUGCACCUUGUUUGACACACAGAACUGUCGCGGCUCCUUCCUAUUGUUAGAAGCCUUAAUUACUAUUGUUCCAAUUCCUCCCUCCAGCGAUCGUCAUUAGGAAGAGCGUUCUUGUUUCUUCCUCCUUCCCCCCAUCCCCCUGAACACGUCUUCAGGGCUGUUCCCUGGCGCUGCCUGCCUCUCACCCGGCUCUACCCUGUUCACUGUGCCCUUCUACCCAGGGCAGCCCCUGACAGCCCACCUCCCUUAUCCCCUGGCCCUGGCCUGCGCUCCCACCUGCUACCUCUUUAGGAAACAAACACAUACCCUUCCCACCCCCAUCCCCAAGUCUCCCCAUUAAAACUCAUGGCUCAAAGCCAGGGAUGCUUUACCUUGUGUGUGGAUUCAAGAACCUGUCCUACCCGCUUCUCUGGUGGUUGUGAGAAUCCAAACCAAGAGAAGGGUGGUGCCUUAAACUGGAAAGUACUGCACACAUUUAGGGGGUGUCCGUGCACCAGCGCCGCAGGCCAUAGCUGGCUGGGGGAAGGCUUGGGCUACCCUGCUGCUCUGCCAUUGACUCCCUGGGAGGAUCUUUGACUUCAGCUUCUCCUCGGUAAGGCUCCGUGGUGGGCCCGGCACAGCCUGUAUCGGAGUGGAGAACGUAGGUUGGUCCAGAGCACGUUCCACCGGGACCUCUCCGUCUGGAGCCUGUAUCAGAGUGGAGAACGUAGCUCUGUGGCUGUGGGCUGCUGGGAGUGGGCAUCUGGCUCUCCGUGUCCCAAGGCAACUUUGCCACCUUCUCCCCCAGCUUCCCUUCGUUGUCUGCAGCCAACCUGGUCAUUGCCAUAGGCACCAUUGUCAUGGUGACGGGCUUCCUCGGCUGCCUGGGGGCCAUCAAGGAAAACAAGUGCCUCCUCCUCAGCUUUUUCAUCGUCCUGUUGGUCAUCCUCCUAGCAGAGCUGAUCUUACUCAUCCUCUUCUUUGUCUACAUGGACAAGGUGAACGAGAACGCCAAGAAGGACCUGAAGGAAGGCCUGCUGCUGUACCACACCGAGAACAACGUGGGGCUGAAGAACGCCUGGAACAUCAUCCAGGCUGAGAUGCGAUGCUGUGGUGUCACUGACUACACAGACUGGUACCCAGUGCUGGGGGAGAACACGGUUCCCGACCGCUGCUGCAUGGAGAACUCCCAGGGCUGCGGGCGCAACGCCACCACGCCUUUGUGGAGAACGGGCUGCUAUGAAAAGGUGAAGAUGUGGUUCGAUGACAAUAAGCACGUGCUGGGCACGGUGGGGAUGUGCAUCCUCAUCAUGCAGAUCCUGGGCAUGGCCUUCUCCAUGACCCUCUUCCAGCACAUCCACCGGACUGGUAAGAAGUACGACGCAUGAGCGGGCUGGCCGGGAGUGCCCACCCCGCCCUGCUGCCCUGUGGAGGGAAGAGGAUUGAGCUUUGUGUCACCUGCCUGCGCUCUCCAGAUAUGACCCCUGCACCCACCCCCCACAGCCUGCCCUACCCCACCUACCCUGCCUCAGCCUCGGACUUCUCAGUGGGUGGAGUGCCAGGGAGGAGGAGGCACACGGAGACCUGGGGCUCGGGGCCCCUGGAUUCCUGCAUCUGCAUAUGCGUAUUUGCCAAAGACGACAGGGUGGGCUGGGGUGCGCUCCGGAGGAACCCCCGGCACUGAUGGGCUUCUGCCCCUGCCCUUCCUCACACUGACACUUUGUCCCCACAUGGGGUGGGGAGCAGAGUGCCCGCCCCGUGGAGAUACCGCCCCAGCGGGGGCUGCGACAUCCAUGGCCACCAUGGGGCACCUGGCGGGGCGGGGGUCUGCCGGCCUCUGGGCAAGGCCCCUGGAGCAUCUCGCCCAGGCUUUUUAUACCUUACAAUGUAACUUUUUUAUUUUAUUUUACUCUAUGAUUAUUCAGGAAUAUUAUCUCUCAGAUAAGUUUAGGGUUAGAUUUCUGAUUUGUAACUUUUUACUGUGUUGAUUUCUUUAAUGGUUUGACUUUUUUUCCCUGAGGGUGAGGGAUGGGUGGGAAGAGAGGACAUCUGUCCAGUCUCAAUCAGGACAGACCACCGUGCGACACCCAGGAGGCUCUCGGAUGGGGCGCGCCUGCGCCCUCAGAACGUGUGGGAAGGAGGGGGCGUGGACAGGACACGGGACCUUGCCAGGCCUGGUGUCUGAGGACAGGAGCCUGGGAGAGGCGGGUGGAGCGUGAAGCAGGCUGGAGGUGCCCCUGCACGGGAGGUGGCGUUUGCUAACCAAUCGAGCUGGAAAUGCCAGGGCAGGGGGGCCCCACGGUGCUGUGGCAGAGCUAGAGGGGUCCUUAGACUUUUCACUGAUGAGCAGUUGUUGGUUUUUUCUUUCUCCCUUCCUCCCGCUCUCUGCUGGCACGCGAGGCUUCCCCUUCCACCCCAUGUGGGUAUUCCCACAACAGGUUCUGCACACCCCAGUUAUUUCACAGACAUUCCUGCUAGAAACUGUCAGACAAAUACCUCUCUAGUUCGGAUGCUGCUCACUUUCCCCCUUGCUUCUGGAAGGGGAAGCAGUCCUUAGGUUUUGCUGUGCUGGGACAGUGGCAGGGGACCCACAGGGGUGAGGACCCACGGUCCUCCCCGCCAGCCUUGCUCAGCUGUGGGUUGCCCUGCUGGGAAGGAGGGAAUCACGUCCACCUGGGUCCCAAGAUCUUCGCCUCCUUCCCUGGGGCCACGGACAUCAGCAGUGGGUUGGGUGGCGAUUAUAUCAUCUGUGAUCCCAAGGAGAAGAAAUACAGAAAACCCAAGAGAGGUCAGACUGGCUCUUGUUACCGGAGCCACGGGAAGAAAGCAGCCGGAGUCACGCACGUGCAGAGCUGGGCAUGGGAGAGAAACGGGCUGGGGAGUGAGGCCAGGAGUGGGAUUCAGCUGCAGCAGGGCGCCCCCUCCAAACUGCAGCUGGUCUGGCUUACUGUUUUGCCGUUCAAAAAGGUCGCGAAUCCGUGGGACUGAGCACGGGGACCUCACCCGCUAGCCAGCGUCUGCUGCACUUGAUCAGGUGGGGCCUUGGUGGGCGGCUGCCUUUCCUAUACAGUUUGUCUUGUCACCCUGGUUUCCCACUGGGGCCAGGUCUCUUCUCCAGCCUCCACCUGCCUGUCUGAUCCAAGAGCUGAGACACGGCCACCCAGCACCAGUCACUCCUCUGUUCACCUUAAGUAACACACAAAUCGGGAACAGGAGGACAGAACCGUUGGCAUUAUCAGGAUUCGUGUUUUGUGGGGGUGGGAGUGGAGAGUAGGGUGGUCUUGUGAGUUGUGCAGGGUGAAGACCGCUUCCCUGAGACAGGGGCAGUGGUGCUGAUGGAAUGUGGGGGAGGCCCACAUUUGAGCAAAGCUGCCCUGCCCUUGUCCCCUGGCCUGGCUUCCUGGUAAGGAGUUUCAGCCGCCUCCGCAGGAACCCCCAAAGUGCAGAUUCCGGAGCAGACACAUCCGGGCGGAGAGACUCAGCAGACAAGUGCUGCAGUUGCACGGUGGGACCCGGGGCCUCGUGCGUUUUUUGCUGUGGGUGGGGUGGGUGGGUUGGUUUAUGCCUAUCAAUGCAAUUUUUAAUUUUUGUUAAUAUCAACAGCAAAAGCCUAGUGCAUUGGGAGAUGUGCAACCUCCCUGAAAAUCUUUUCUGUUUCUGGAGUACUUCAGGGGUGGCCUCUGGCCCCAGAGCCUUUGCCACAGUGCUCCCACCAGCCCCCACCUCAUCCGUCUGUUUGCAGAGCCUCAUCUACAGGUCCCCACGCUGCCUUCUUUACUCACUCUGCGCUUGGCCGUUUUGUUAUUUGGCUUAGUCUACAUUGGGCGGAAGUCUGUGUGCACAGAGUGGGUGUUCCUUCGAGCCCCUUCCACUCAGAGGGCCACACCCAGCGAUGCCAGUGAAGGUGGCACAGCCUCUCUUCAGUUUCUCCUGACUGUGAUCUCACUGGGGUAGAAUUCCCCUGAGAGAAUUCCCUCACUCACGGCUCCCUUUGCCAGAGUCAGUUCAAUCAGGUCUGAUGUGAGCAAUUUACACACUUGUCUCAGAAAGUCCCUCAGGGUUUGUAGAGGACUGCAGGGGGGCAUCCGCUGCAGACUCAGCCUUUCUCUGCAGCCAUCCUGCAGUGGGGGUGAGCGGGCACAGGCUGAGAACUGCUCUUGGGUGGUGGAAGCAGGUGUCACGGUGCAAGUCUCCCCCUGCACCCCUCCCCCAGCUUGAGCCGUGUCACCCCCCUCUCCCUCCAGCAUGGGCCUGUGUCUCAGGCUCUCUGGAAGGUGGCCCUGCCCCGGACCCUCUUGCAGGUGUCCUGGUUUGACUUGGAACUAGAUGGCCAUCUUUCCAGGCUUUGGUGGCCCAAGAGCAGUCUGGGUGGAUGGAAGUGGCUGUCCCCUCCUCUCCAGCCCCUGCCCACCCACUGGUGGAGGUGCUAACUAGCAGGGACGUGGCAUAGGAUGGGAGCUGGGCGUGAGGUGCUUGGGGUCCAUUCUUUGUCCCUCAGCUUCUCAGAGUCCGGCCAGCCCUUGUGUUCCCGUGCCCCACACUUUCCUCCUCCCCACUGCAGUGAGUCAAUAGUCCAGGGUGGGGCCUGGCCUCCCUGCCCUGAUUGGGGACUCAGGAGGUGAGGCCUGGGGGGCUUCCUGCCCCCUCCUUGCCCACCUGCCUGCCCCCGGGCAGCACGGGAGGGAGAGCAGGGUGAGCACGCUUGUUGGUUUCAGAUGCACUUUCUGCUUGCAUUGCCGUAUCUGUGCGUUCCUUCAUCCUGGUCCUGGCUUUAUGGAACACCAUGUUUUUAGCAUGUUUUUAAAUAAAAACGGAUAAAGUGUCAAAAGCA